GGGGAGCCAUGGGAGCUGGGGUCAGGGCCGCUGUUGCUGCAGUCGGCCCUACACCUGCCUGGGAGGGCUGGACCAGUCCUGAAAGCCCCCGGUGGUGGUGCCAUGUCUGCCCACCAGCCCGCCUGUCGCUUGGCACCAGUGGAGUCUUCGCUUGCAAAGCGGGAUUAGACAUCAAAGCCCUAACACCCAGACUGUUCAAUUCAUUCCAGAACUGAAGAAUAGAGCCUGUUGCUGCUGGAGCUGAUUCCCUUCCCCUCCUCAUCUCCCACCUCCUUUCAGUCUCACAUACACACACAGAUGCUGCCACAGACACACGCGAGCGCAAAUAUUUACACACUGCCACACCGAAGAAAUCCAUGCACGUUUUCCUGCAAACGCGCGCGCGCACACGUACUUCGGCGGGCGCCCACGUCCUCUGUCUCACCAACAGACACAGACAUUUACACUUCUAGGCCAGGAAAGCGCUAACCAGGGCCCUGUGACUCUACGCAGGUUCCAGAACACGCCUUCUACAUUUGUUACUGAACCGAUCAGCGAACACAGACAAACGUGCCAACACUUAAGUCUACUGGCUGGACUUCAUCUCCAUGGCAACAAGCAUGGAAGGCAAAGAGUUGAUUCCAGAAGGAACUGUGAAGAGCCACAACAAUGUGCCAGUGAAUAAUGAGUAGUACCUACUGUGGCAACUCUUCAGCUAAGAUGAGUGUCAACGAAGUAUCAGCUUUCUCAUUGACUCUGGAGCAAAAAACUGGCUUUGCUUUUGUUGGGAUUUUGUGUAUCUUCUUGGGACUUCUUAUUAUCCGAUGCUUCAAAAUCCUGCUAGACCCAUAUAGUAGCAUGCCUUCCUCUACAUGGGAAGAUGAAGUUGAAGAGUUUGAUAAAGGGACAUUUGAAUAUGCACUCGCGUGAGAGUUCCAGCUAUAUGGUUUUUAUGGUUGUGCCAUCGGGACACAUUCUGGAUACAAUUGUAACUACCUUGAGGGUGUGGGAGAGAGGCUCAUUUUGUUCAGUGAAUUCAAUAAACAUCUGUGACUAAUUUCUUCACCAUGCUGUGUAAAUGAUAAACUAUUGUUGGGAUUCCUCACUUUCCUCUGUUCCCACUUAGAGGUUUCCAAUGAAUAGAGCAUAAGGAUGGCUGCCGCCAUGUUUACCAUCUUUAUUCUUAUCUUGAACAACUGCCUUGAAUUUCUGCUUCCUUUCUUGUGCUAAUAAACUGUGCCAAAGGCAUCUUGCUCUCUCCCCUCUGAAAAGCCCAGGCAUCCCCUCCACAUUCCUGACUCAGACCCCUUUAGCUUUAGUGAGUCAGGUCUUAAACAGAGAAUUUAGUCCAAAGAAUAAUCAAAAUAUUAUUUGUCUAAUAAUAACCAUAGGCCCAAAAGGUUCACAGGUGAAAAAAUAUCUCAAAAAUCUAACACCCAAAGCCUACAAGUAGUCACAGGCCCUAAAGCUCCCCAAAUUUCACAGAGCCCUGACCCUCCUAUCUCUUCUGUUUGUCGAAUCUCUUGCAGUAAAAUCCCAUAGCUUGGAAUCCAAACCAGAUCUGCCUCAUACUGAUGCUCCCUCCCCUACCCCUUGCAUAAAUAGAAUUUAAAAGGGAGUUUCCAGCAUGACCUAGUGGAAAGAGUACUCUAAGCAGAAACAAAGACAGUCUCAGCUGUGCCACCAGUAGAGCUAUGCUCUAAUGGGUAAGUCAUCUAAUCUCUGUGAGCUUCAGUGAAGAGUAGUGUUAACAUCCUUUUCAAUUCUAGUGCCCUAUGAAUGCUACAAAUGUAUCUGAAAACCCAGAGAUCUGAAAUGAAUGAGGAUUUAAGAUAUCAUGAAAAGUUUUUCAGAUUAGGAGCCUAAACUCAGAGAUUUGAAUUCUAAUGUUAGCUUAGCCAAGAACUAGCUUUAUGACCUAGAAAGUUACCUAAAGGGAACCUAUAUUGCACAACAAGAAUUAAGAAACCCAUCCUGCAUGUCUUCAGCAAUAUUGAGAGGGCCAAUUAGAUAUAAUGAAUGUGAAAGCAUUUUGUAAACCAUAAAACAGUAUCUAAACAUACCUUGCUAUCAAUAUUUAUUGUCCUCAUCAGUAGCAGUAAUAGAGAUUCUCAAACCCUAAGAAGCAAUGGCUUAGUGUAAAUUAUUCAAUCUCUCUAGUAUUUCAUUCUCUUCAAUUGAGAAAUAAAAAGAUAAAAUUAUAUAGUUCUAAAUUCUUUCCAACUACAAACUUCUGACUCUCUAUGAGUCAGAAUGGAGGAACAUAGCAGGAGAUAAAUACAAAAAUAUUUAUGUCCUUUGAAAACACAGAACUGCAAAACAUACCAUGAAGGAACAAGACUAAUAUUACCAAGAGGUAGCACUAAGUUAGUUACUUUCAAUUUAUUUGAUACUCUUAUAAAUUCUUUGAGUUGGAGACUACUAUUUCCAUUUUAUUUUUAAUCUUAAUUUUGCAGAAGAGAAACUGAAGCUAAGAGAAAUUAACUAGCUUCCCAAGGUCACCAUAGCUAGGGAAUGGUUAUGUUAGGGAUUGAACUUGGGCAGUUUGAUUUCUGCUGUAUCCCUAGACACUGUCCUCAACACUUCUACAUAGCUUAUAGGCAUGGUUACUGCUCAGGUCUAUGGAAUUCCAAAACCAGCUGUCUCUGUGAGAUUCCUUGAUGCUUUCCAUCUCAUAAUAGAUUUAGAACAUAUCUGUUAUUAGCUAUGGAUCUUCUGGACCAAAUCCUCACCUCAAGGAGGCUCUCUGUACCCCAGUUGGUUCAAGAGUGUAGGCCUGGUACACCUCAUAGCCAGUUAGUAACUUGGCCCAAGAACAGGCCACUGGGCCAAGUUCAACUGAACAUACUGAAAAUUGUGUGUGCCAGGAAACUAGGUCUCUUUGUUGACCAAGGCUUUUAAAGUACCAGAUGUUUCAUUUGUCUCCCAGAGAAGACACCCACCAAGACCCUCCAUUUUGAUGACUAGAACAAACCAAGGCCAGAUCUUUAUUUCAAAGGAAGAAAGACCUCUACAACCAAGAAAACUUUAUGAAAUAUGAGCAUUGUUUCUGGAAGUUCAACUCCCAUAAGCUUUUCAAGUAUAUUAACUCUACCAUAAUAUUAUUUCCAAAUCCACUAAAGAAAAAUUCUAUUAACCAAAA